CUCAAAGGCUCAGCUCAGGCCCAGGCCCCCAGGAGAGCUCUCGGCUGGGAUGGACCGAGGGAGGCUGUGAGGGAGGCUUAGCCAGAGGGCACCCAGCCCUCAGAGGGGAGGAGGCCAACAGGGGUUCUCCUAGGCGUGGCCACCCGUUCUCCCCUGCCUGGCAUGCAGAAGGCACCAGGUGGGCAGAGAGAUGGUUCCAGGGAAUCCACUGGGCGGAAGCAGGAGAGUGGGAGUGGAAGGGUGCACUCCAUGGACGGCCCCCGCCCCUCACCCGCCUCCCGUGCUCCUUCCAGGACACUCUGGAGGCUCCAGCCUCCCACCCACAGGGCCGCCCUCCACACCUGGUCUGGGAAGAUACCUGGAGGUUUUGAUUGGGGUCUCGGUGGCCUUCGUCCUGCUGCUCUUCCUCCUCCUCUUCCUCCUCCUCCGACGUCAGCGUCACAGCAAACACAGGACAUCUGACCAGAGAAAGACUGAUUUCCAGCGUCCUGCAGGGGCUGCGGAGACAGAGCCCAAGGACAGGGGCCUGCUGAGGAGGUCCAGCCCAGCUGCUGACGUCCAGGAAGAAAACCUCUGUAAGAGGAAGAGAGGGGACAAAUGGGGGUGCUGGAGAGACAGGAGUCCCAAAAUUUCAGUAGCAACAGGGAGGGGCUGGGAAGGGUCUGGGGCUCCGUGGAAGAUGGUCUUGCCCCACACUGUGGGACCUCCCUGCAUUCGGUGGCCCCAUCUGGGAGCAGGGCAGGGGGCCAGCAGGACUGAGAGGUCUCAGAGAACCAGGAGACGAACCCCUUGCUCUGCCCCAGCAGAUGCUGCCGUGAAGGACACACAGUCUGAGGACAGGGUGGAGCUGGACAGUCAGCAGAGCCCACACGAUGAAGACCCCCAGGCAGUGACGUAUGCCCCGGUGAAACACUCCAGUCCUAGGAGAGAAAUGGCCUCUCCUCCCUCCUCACUGUCUGGGGAAUUCCUGGACACAAAGGACAGACAGGUGGAAGAGGACAGGCAGAUGGACACUGAGGCUGCUGCAUCUGAAGCCUCCCAGGAUGUGACCUACGCCCAGCUGCACAGCUUGACCCUUAGACGGAAGGCAACUGAGCCUCCUCCAUCCCAGGAAGGGGAACCUCCAGCUGAGCCCAGCAUCUACGCCACUCUGGCCAUCCACUAGCCCGGGGGGUACGCAGACCCCACACUCAGCAGAAGGAGACUCAGGACUGCUGAAGGCACGGGAGCUGCCCCCAGUGGACACCAGUGAACCCCAGUCAGCCUGGACCCCUAACACAGACCAUGAGGAGACGCUGGGAACUUGUGGGACUCACCUGACUCAAAGAUGACUAAUAUCGUCCCAUUUUGGAAAUAAAGCAACAGACUUCUCAACAAUCAA